AGUUUUCUCCAAAGGAGAAGGAGUGCACUUAGAGGGAGCUGUGUUUUGGUGACCUCUGAAACUCAGUACUGCAGCGAAUGAGCUCCUGACCUUGAGGAGUACUUAACAGAAUUAUGUCUCGAAGAAUCAUUGUGGGAACCCUUCAAAGAACCCAGCGAAACAUGAAUUCUGGAAUCUCGCAAGUCUUCCAGAGGGAACUCACCUGCCCCAUCUGCAUGAACUACUUCAUAGACCCGGUCACCAUAGACUGUGGGCACAGCUUUUGCAGGCCCUGUUUCUACCUCAACUGGCAAGACAUCCCAAUUCUUACUCAGUGCUUUGAAUGCAUAAAGACAAUACAGCAGAGAAACCUCAAAACUAACAUUCGAUUGAAGAAGAUGGCUUCCCUUGCCAGAAAAGCCAGUCUCUGGCUAUUCCUGAGCUCUGAGGAGCAAAUGUGUGGCAUUCACAGGGAGACAAAGAAGAUGUUCUGUGAAGUGGACAGGAGCCUGCUCUGUUUGCUGUGCUCCAGCUCUCAGGAGCACCGGUAUCACAGACACUGUCCCGCUGAGUGGGCUGCUGAGGAACACUGGGAGAAGCUUUUAAAGAAAAUGCAGUCUUUAUGGGAAAAAGCUUGUGAAAAUCAGAGAAACCUGAAUGUGGAAACCACCAGAAUCAGCCACUGGAAGGCUUUUGGAGACAUAUUAUACAGGAGUGAGUCCGUGCUGCUGCACAUGCCCCAGCCUCUGAAUCUAGCGCUCAGGGCAGGGCCCAUCACUGGACUGAGGGACAGGCUCAACCAAUUCUGAGUGGAUAUUACUCUGCAUCACAAUGAAGCCAACAGUCAUAUCUUCCGAUGUGGAGAUUUGAGAAGCAUUUGUAUUGGAUGUGACCGUCAAAAUCCGCCCCAUAUCACUGCAACACCUACAAGUUUUCUUGCAUGGGGUGCUCAGACUUUCACCUCUGGCAAAUAUUACUGGGAGGUCCAUGUGGGGGACUCUUGGAAUUGGGCUUUUGGUGUCUGUAAUAAGUAUUGGAAAGGGAAGAAUCAGAAUGGCAAUAUAUAUGGAGAGGAGGGACUCUUUAGUCUUGGGUGUGUUAAGAACGACAUUCAGUGCAGUCUCUUUACCACCUCCCCAAUUACACUGCAGUAUGUCCCAAGACCUACCAACCAUGUAGAAUUAUUCCUGGAUUGUGAAGCUAGAACUGUGAGCUUCGUUGAUGUUAGUCAAAGCUCCCCUAUAUACACCAUCCCUAAUUGCUCCUUCUCACUUCCUCUCAGACCUAUCUUUUUCUGUAUUCUCCUCUGACCAGAGACAAAUCAGAAAUGUGUUCAUCUGCUGUGGGAACCCCUUUAUCCCAGAAAGCCCUCUUCCUUGUGCCUUAUCAAACAGGACAAAUAGGUUCGGUUUUAUGUCUUGAAUUGCAUUCUAAUGUUAUUAAAACUCAUUUAUUGUGUUACUAUUAAAUGUAGUAAAAACACUAAAA